CCACCCGCACCACUCGCUUGAGCAGGUGGGGCAGAGGUGGGCACCCUCCUCUCUCAGCCCCCCAAGGGCUCUGAAGUUGCUGCGCUCAGAGGACGUGUACCCAGUGUCCUGAGAAGCAGCCUCAGGGCAGUCACUCCUCACCAGUCACAUCCCACUUUGCACAGAGCUCGCACUGCCCCACUCUGGAUGUGGGUGCUGGGGCAAGGCUCUCCUGGGACUCCAGUCAGGACAGUACAGCAGCUGGUGGAAGCUUCUGGUAGCAGAUGCCUCCAUUGCCUCAGAAUCCUGGCCACCGGCUCAGGCUGUCCAGAGGGAAAGGGAAGCACAUUCCUUCCCGCAGAAACGAGACUCCGUGGCCUGCUGGGACAGGCGCUCCAGUGGCAACAAGAAUGGAAGCUGUCAUGUGUUUAAACAGGAGGUUGGGUUAAAGUGUAAGGCCAGAAAUACCCCAGAUAAUUCUAUGAUGACAAAGGGCACCGGGAGGUCCUUGGGAAGUGGGGGCCAGCAGGUGCUGGGAAACAGCCAGGGCCCUUGGGGAGGUUUCUUGGCUGGAGAGCUCUUGUUUGAAACAAGGAGGAACCAGGCCUGGGAGCCUAGAGACACAAGCAGGUCGGGAAUAAGGGAGCAUCCAGAGCCCUUGCUGCAGGCCAUGUCCCAGGAAGGAGGCGACGAGCAGCCGGGAGAGAUGGAGACCAUUCCUUGAGGUUCUUUCUCCAAGGCCUUGACUUUCCCACCCCGGAGCAGCAAGCACUUGACCAAAGGUUGAUCAAUAGCUUCAGCACUCCCUGCGCAGCUCUGGACAGCUGACUUAGCUCUACCUCAGUUCCGUCACCCGAGAAGCACAGGUAACGCCAAUCCGAGUGGCACAGGCUGUUGCUGAAGAUGAAGUUGGAUGAGCAACGUAAAGCACUGAGAACAGGGCCUGGCACGGGUCAGCUCUCGGGGUGUCCGCUCCUGUCAUCACCGUCGUCAUGGUCGGCAGCAAGCCUCCCUGACUGGGUGGACUCCUGCAGCUCCUUCCCUGGGUCCAGUGGGGAAGCCGUGUCUAUAUACCACACUGGGACGAGGACCUGAAAGAGACUUGGGUAUGGCCAGGACUGCCCACUUCCUCUCACUCAGCAGAUGCUGACCGAGAACCCACGUGCACCAGGCACUCUCAGCACUAGAGACUCAACAGCAAGACAAGAUGGGAGCUUACGUUCUAGGAGGAAGACCUGCAAGAGGUCCACAAGCGGAUCGGUAUAUAAUGACACGUCGUGGCGUGCAAGGUCAAUAAAAAUAAGGAGGUGGAGAGUGACAGGGUCAAGGGAGGCCUUCGUGGGGACGUGAUCCCUGGGCAGAGUCCUGAAGGAAUGAAUAACCCACACAGGUAGAGCCAAGGGAAGAGGGCCUGAAACACAGUGGACAGCAAGCGCGGAGGCCCUAAGGUGGUGCACGCUGACCAGAGAUGCAGGAGAGGCAGCAGGAGGGUGGAGAAGCCAUCUUCAGUCCCCUCGGCCACUCCAGCUGCUGAAUAAUGCCAUGUUAUGGCUGUGAAGAAAUUUCACCUCCCUGAGCUUUUCUGACCUUGAGAUUGGCAGGGCACAUGACACACCCAUUUUAUAAAUGGGCAUGUCCAUUUGAUAAAGGAGGAAGAGUUCAGCUCCUCUUCUCCAAGUCCAGGGCCUUGUCUCCACAGCGAAGCCUCCCCAUGCCCCACUCAUUCCUUUGCCCACCCCCGUGCCCGCCACCAAACUAGAAGGUGACCGAAACAGCCCCCACUCCGGAACCGUUGCCCAUCCACUCUUUGCUUGGCUGUCUGUGAGCCUAGUGCAAAUGGGGCGGCCUCACUGUCUCCUGACACCAUUCAAAGGGCCACAGGGCAGUGGGCACCUACGGGUGGGACUUGAGGACCAGUGUGCUCCUACUUGGUACUGCAGUUACGAGGAAAACCCUUGAAAUGUCCCAAUAGAGGCAGUGAUUUGAAUUUGUUCCCAUUUUAUGCCAGCUCCUAAGCCUCAGCCAGUUACUGAUGUGUAAACACACCUUUCCUACAAAGCACUGAUCACAAAAGGAAAGCGUUCCUUCCCUGGGAGCCGCCGUCACCACCACCAUGCCCGGCCAUGUCAAAAUCUGCCGUGAAGAUAUCCUUGGACUUACUCUCCAAUCCCCUCUGUGAGCAAGACCAGGACCUUCUGAACAUGGUGACGGCCCUGGACACGGCCAUGAAGCGGAUGGAUGCCUUCAAUCAGGAAAAGGUGAACCAGAUCCAGAAGACUGUGAUCGAGCCCUUAAAAAAGUUCGGCAGUGUCUUCCCGAGCCUCAACAUGGCUGUGAAGAGGCGGGAACAGGCCUUGCAGGACUACAGGAGGCUGCAGGCCAAGGUGGAGAAGUAUGAGGAAAAGGAGAAGACGGGGCCAGUGCUGGCCAAGCUCCACCAGGCACGAGAGGAGCUGCGGCCUGUGCGGGAGGACUUUGAAGCCAAGAACAGGCAGCUGCUGGAGGAGAUGCCGCGCUUCUACGGCAGCCGCCUCGACUACUUCCAGCCCAGCUUUGAGUCCCUCAUCCGAGCUCAGGUUGUGUACUACUCGGAAAUGCACAAGAUCUUUGGAGACCUGUCCCAUCAGCUUGACCAGCCAGGCCACUCCGAUGAGCAGCGGGAGCGGGAGAACGAGGCCAAACUCAGUGAGCUCCGGGCCCUCUCCAUUGUGGCCGAUGACUGAAUCCCCGUCACUCUUGGAGGACUCCUGUGACGUGGUCAGCCUCAUUCAUCCUUGCCCUUCUCAGGGCUAGCUGCUCCUCUCACAGGCUGGGGACAGAGGUGGCCCUGGUUCACUUGCCGGCCCUUUGCAAUGAAUGACUCUUCCUGAGCCUGGCACCAGGAGCCCUAGGCAGGCCGCCGUCUCCCCACUCACAGCCCCAGCAGGUAAGCAGUGUAGACAAACCCUUGGGGCUUUUUUAUUUGGAGAACCGUCCAGCAUGCAUCCUGGCCCACGGCCUGAGCAAGCUGCAGCCCUUCUGAGGCCAUGGGCUUCGUUGGCUAAGUUGGGGGUCUUAGCCUUGCAUGCGUUGUGGGCAUCAAAUCUACCUCCAAAAGACCCAUCCUGGGGAGCCCUCUGGCCCCUCGUUGCCUUUUCACUUCAAAACCUCUUUUUUCUGGGAGAGGCCCUGAACCCUGUGCGGGAGAGCUGGUCCUCCAGCCCUGGCAGGCCCUCAGCCAGCUUCCCAGCAAGACAAAGGGCACCCUUGUGGCUUUGGGACCUAAGUGGUUGGGGUUCCCGAGGUCACUGAGGACUGGUACCUCGGGAACGCAAGCUGUCAGUGGAACUGUCCCACAAGAAUUCACAGGUCUCAAAGCAGGAACAGUGGGUUUGUGUCUCACCUGAGUAUCUGGAAUUUUAUUUUUUCAAGUAAAAUUUUCAAUGAAACGUCCACAUAGUAUUGUGCUGUAACUUAGGCGAGCAGAGGAAACCCCUUCCUGGGCCUGCUGCCCUCCACGGAGCAGCAGCACCCUCCAGCAGGCAGCCCAGCAUGCCAGGGGUGUGUGCGCACCUCCCCGGCCCUGGCCCACCUUCUGGAGCGAACUGCACCGUGGUCCAGCAGAGGCGCUGGGUGGGAGGGCACGCGGGCAAGCCUAGGAGAGUAGGAAGAGCUGUGGAGGACACACUCUCAGUUUGUUUUUGACUUUGGUUUAUUUAAAAAACAAGCCAAAAAAAAAAAAAAAAAA